GGGAGCUAAGCCAGACCCGGGUGGCGGUGGCAGCUGCGAAACCCAGGGAGCCGAUGCCACGUGACCCAAUGUGGACUUCUUUUAAACCUUUCUAAUGCCCAUAACCCAGCCUCAGACCCAUGGAGCCCACGAGAGACUGCCCGCUGUUCGGGGGCGCCUUUUCCGCCAUCCUCCCCAUGGGGGCCAUUGACGUAAGCGACCUCCGACCGGUCCCGGACAAUCAAGAAGUUUUCUGCCAUCCCGUGACGGACCAGAGCCUGAUAGUGGAACUUCUCGAGCUGCAGGCCCACGUACGGGGCGAAGCGGCUGCGCGGUACCACUUUGAGGAUGUUGGUGGCGUGCAGGGGGCUAGGGCUGUCCAUGUGGAGUCUGUUCAGCCUCUCAGUUUGGAGAACCUGGCCCUGAGGGGCCGCUGUCAAGAAGCCUGGGUCCUCUCUGGCAAGCAGCAGAUAGCUAAGGAAAACCAGCAGGUGAGGGCCCGAGAGUGUGUAAUGUCCUGGAAGGGCGGUAGCGGGGACGCAGAGAUCCAGGUAAGCAUCCUGACUCUGAUCCCCUUAGGUAGCAAAGGACGUGACACUUCAUCAGGCCUUGCUGAGGCUGCCCCAGUACCAGACUGAUCUCUUGCUUACCUUCAAUCAGCCCCCGUAAGGAGGAAGGAACGGGCGGGUAUCUCAUGACUGGGUUCCCAGGAGAAUCGGGCUGGGAGGGACAGAACAGGGAGACUCACUGGUGGGAUCCUCCAAGGAAGCAGGAGUGGGCCAGAGGUUUGGGGUAACUGAUACCCAGGUCCUCUGGGGAACAGGAAUUGGCAAUUUCCAAACCUCAGGCCUGGAUGAUGUUCUGUCUCCAUCUGUUCCCCCACCCCAAGCCCUGACAACAGGUCAUCUCUUGGCCCCGAAAAUCUGUCACCUGCACCCUGGAGCCUGGGUGACUUUGAACAGCUGGUGACCAGUCUGACCCUUCACGAUCCUAACAUCUUUGGUCCCCAGUAAAGGCGCUGAAGCACUGCAUGAUGUUGCUGAGAACUUGGGGACUCGGUUCUGUGAGGGGGAAAAGAGGUUGAAAAGAGGGUUUCCUCUUAUUUCUUCCCUGUGCGUAAACAUAAGACAAUCCCUCUUCAGAAUAAACUUGCUUUAUAAUCAA